CAUUGCUUAUAACAGAAUACCUGAAACUGGGUAAUUUCUAAAGAAAAGGAAAUUAUUUUUUACAGUUAUGGAGGCUGGAGGUCCAAAGUUGAGGAGCCGUAUCUGAUGAGGGCCUUCUUGCUGGUGGGACCCUGCAGGUUCCGAGGCAGCACAGGGCAUCACGUGGCAAGGGGGUGGAGCAUGCUAAUAUGCUCGCUCAGGCCUCUCUUCCUCUUCUUCUGAAGCCACCAGUUCCCCUCCCAUGACAGCCUAUUAAUCAUAGAUUAAUCCAUUUGUGAAGGCAGAUCCUUUAUGACCCAAACACCUCUUAAAGGUCCCGCCUCUCAAUACUGUGACAUUAGGGAUUAAAUUUCAACAUGAGUUUUGGAAAAGACAAAUAUGCAAAUCAUAGUAUGGGUCUGUGCCUGUUUCCUCUGUCUUUCUCCCUAUCCUAUACAACUAGUACUAAAAUGUGAAAGGAUUCCUAAUCAGCAAAAAUCCAGUAGGAUGCUUGUCUCAUUAGAUUCUGUUCUUUAAACAUUUAUUCUGUUCUCUGAUUUGUGGUUUGAAAAGAGGAAAACUCAGUAAAGAAUUGCCCAUCUCAGGGAGUUAAGCACCAUGGGUUAGCACACACAGUGCCCUAAGGUUACUUUCUAGCUCAUCUCCUCUUUGGCUGCAUGUCUUUGGGCAAGUAACACAACUCACUAAACCUCAGGUUUGUCAUUUUAAGAUGGGACUGUCAUGAAGAAGCAGAUAUUUAAGUUUAUAAAAUGAUUGAUAAAUGAUGGCCAUGACAUUGGCUGAUGUUGAGAGGGCUAACAUUGUUCUCCAGGGCAAAGCCCAUGACCUCGAUGAUAGAGUAGACUGCAUUUUGAUUUAUGACUCGCACACUGACAGCGUGAUGUGAACCAGCCUCACAUUCAUUGAACCAGUGCCUGUCGGGUGCUGGCUUUUUGCCAGGCCACAUGCUGGGCUCUGGAGGAUGAGAGGAACCAGACUCUGCUCCAGUGUAAUAUACAAUCCAGGCAUGGAUGCAGGCCUCAUGACACACGAGUCACUACACUAUGAUAAGCCUCAGGGUGCAGGGCUGUACAGAGUCCUACAAGAGCCAGGUAGAGAAAGGGUUAGUUCUACCUGGGGGAGAAGUCAGGAGACACCUCAGAAGAAAGGUGACUUCAUCCUCAUUCAGUGACUGAGCAUAAAAAUGAGAAGACAACAGACUGCUUUCUCUUUCCUGUGUUUUGAGAGUUAGUAUAGAGCAUGGUGAUGAUGAGUAUAGACUCUGGAGCUGCGCUGUCUGGGUCAAAAUCCACGCUCUUCCAUUUAUCAGCUGUGUGACUCUAAACAAACCUCUGUUUGUGCCUCAAUUUCUUUAUCUGUGAAAUAGGGAUGAUAACCUUGUACAUUCCUUCCAGAGGAUAAAAUACCCAGGACAGUACCUUGCUUAAAACUAAGGCCUAUGUGACUGCUUGUUGUUGUUGUAAUUGAGGCUUCCUUCCUACAGCAAGGGAGUUCUCAUAGGAUGGACCCCUGGAGCCCUCCUCCACCUGCCACAACACUGUGGAGUUCCAGGGCCUUAGUGAAGUACAGGAUUUGGACUAAAUCCUUGGUCUGCUGUGUAAUUAUCCUUGUAUUUUGUAUCUCCAUACAGCAUCUUCAUUUGAUUUACAUCCAUAUCUCAAAGGAACAGAUGGCUUUUAUUUGUCAAAUAAUUAUUUGAAAGGGAAAAUAGGUUCUGUUGAGUUCUGGACUCUGUCUCCAUAAUUUUAAGCCAAGUACCUCAUUUUUGUUAAUAAUAAUAGCUGCUAUUUACUAAAAGCUCCCCACGUGCUGGGCACAAUGCUUAGCAUUUUAUAUGCAUCAUUUGCUACAUCUCACUGCAGCCCAAAGCUGGAUGUUAUUAGUGUCUUCAUUCUACAGAUGAGGAAGGUAAGGCUCGGAAGCGAUAUAGCUAGAAGAUGGUGGAGCCAAGAUGGAAACCCAGGUUUGUCCAAUUCCAGAGUCACUUUGCUUAACCACUCCACUUCCAUUUUCAUAAGAAAGGGUACCAAUUUCCCUCUCCUGUUUCACUUCUGCGCUAACACAGAGGGACUUGUCUGCAGGUGACAUGCCCCCUUUAUGUAUUUUUAAUGAUGAGGAAAGCUGAACCUGGGCCCCUGCAGUCAUAGCCGAGUGCCACUGUUCAGCUGGUAGCACUCACCUGACCACGCGGGGCUCAGGGAGAAAAAGCCUCCGAAGGCUGUUCCUGAAAAACCAGUGCUUUAUAAAGUGACUUAAUGGAAUGAAAUAUUUCAAAGAGGGGAAUCCAGUCAUUCCCAACAUCACUGGGGAUAUGGGACAUAGAAAUCUUGUGAUUGAAAUACAAAGGGAAGGAGAGAAAGCUCCGACAGAGAAAGGCUUCUGGGAUGAAAGAGGGAAACAGACUAAGUGGCUAAGAGGGAGCAUUAGAGGAGAAGGGGAGGAAAUCUUAAGAGGGUGAAGCACGGAACCUGCCAUUUGCAACAACCAGGCUGGGGCUUAGUCCUGAGGACAUGAAUGGUCUCUUACCCCAGUGCACCAAGGCUGCCAUGUGGCAGGCGUUCAGUAAAUGUUUACUCAUUUAUAAAAGAAUAUGGGCUGGGAUCGGGUAGGAUGGGUAACAAGCAAUUAUUGAGCACCUGAUGUGUGCCAAGCACUUAAUAUUCUUGGACAAUGCUCAUAACUCCGCAGGGUAGGUGCUAACCCCAUUUAAAUGAGGAAAACUAAGGUUUGGAGGGUUAAUAUCCAACGUGCCCAAGUCCAACAUCAGGUAGGUAAUGAAACUAGAAUUUCCCUCCAGAGUUAUUUGAUUCUAAAGCUAUACUCUGUCCAUGACAGCUGGCUCCAUCAUCAAAAUGUUAGCUAAGUGCUACCAUAACUUCCAGAUAAUGUCAUUUAACUCAGUUAUAAUGCAUAACUCUUUAAGAAAGCCCUUAAGAAAUGAGGCGAAUUAUAGGCACCUUGGCAGAGUAUCUUAUCCUCUGGAAGGAAUGUACAAGGUUAUCAUCCCUAUUUCACAGAUAAAGAAAUUGAGGCACAAAGAGAGGUUUGUUUAAAGUCACAUGGCUGAUAAAUGGAAGAGCGUGGAUUUCGACUGAGGCAGUGCAGCUCCAGAGUCUAUAUUCAUCAUCACCACUCUCCAUACUAACUCUCAAAACAUAGUAAAGAGAAAGCAGUCUGUUGUCUUCUCAUUUUUAUGCUCAGUCACUGAAUGAGGACGAAGUUACCUUCUUUCUGAGAUAAUCUCCCAGACCCUCUCUCCGACCUGGAACCAGAUGCUGCUGUUCAAUGAUUUGGUGCUGCAUGGAGAUGUGAAGGAGCUGGCAGAGUCCCCGCCCUUAGUGGUGGUGGAGCUGUAUGACAGCGACGCUGUGGGGAAGCCAGAAUAUUUGGGUGCCACAGUGGCUGCUCCUGUUGUGAAGCUGGCUGACCAGGACUAUGAGCCCCCCAGGUUAUGCUAUCACCCCAUCUUUUGUGGGAAUCUCUCUGGAGGGGAUCUCCUUGCUGUAUUUGAACUGCUGCAGGUUCCUCCUUCUGGGCUGCAAGGCCUCCCACCCGUUGAGCCACCAGACAUCACCCAGAUCUACCCGGUUCCUGCCAACAUUCGGCCGGUGCUGAGCAAAUACCGAGUGGAGGUUCUCUUCUGGGGAGUUCGGGAAAUGAAGAAGGUGCAGCUCCUCUCUGUGGAUCGGCCUCAGGCUCUCAUUGAGUGCGGAGGACAAGGUGUGAAGUCCUGCGUGAUCCAGAGCUACAAGAACAACCCGAACUUCAGCAUCCAGGCAGACGCUUUCGAAGUGGAACUGCCUGAGAACGAGCUUCUGCACCCGCCACUGAGCAUCUGCGUGGUGGACUGGAGAGCUUUUGGGAGGAGUACCCUUGUGGGCACCUACACCAUCAACUACUUGAAGCAGUUUUUGUGUAAACUCAGAGAGCCCCUUGCCCCCAUCACACAGGUGGAUGGAACCCAGCCUGGGCACGAUAUUUCAGAUUCGCUAACAGCCACUGAGUCCUCUGGAGCCCACAGCUCCUCCCAGGAUCCCCCAGCAGAUCACAUUUAUGUGGAUGUUGAGCCACCUCCCACAGUGGUGCCCGACUCUGCCCAGGCCCAGCCGGCCAUCCUGGUUGACGUCCCUGACUCAUCCCCGAUGCUGGAGCCUGAACACACACCUGUAGCCCAGGAGCCACCAAAAGAUGGAAAACCUAAGGAUCCCAGGAAGCCUUCCCGGAGGUCCACUAAGAGGAGAAAGAGGACCAUAGCAGAUGAAUCUGCUGAAAACGUGAUUGACUGGUGGUCUAAGUAUUAUGCCUCCCUGAAGAAAGCCCAGAAGGCAAAGGAGAGAAAUCCCAAGGGAAAAAAAGGCAAUACAGAGGCAAAGCCAGAUGAGGUAGUGGUAGAUAUAGAAGAUGGGCCAAAGAAGAAGAAAGACAAAAUGCUCAAGAAGAAACCCAAAGAUGAUGGAAUCCCCAACCUGGCCAUCUUGCAGAUAUAUGACGGUGAUCUCGAGAGUGAAUUCAACAAUUUUGAAGACUGGGUGAAAACUUUUGAGCUCUUCAGAGGCAAGUCUACGGAAGAUGACCAUGGUCUUGAUGGAGACCGAGUCAUAGGAAAAUUUAAGGGCUCCUUCUGCAUCUACAAAAGCCCCCAGGAUUCUAGCUCUGAGGACAGCGGGCAGCUGAGAAUCCAGCAAGGGAUUCCGCCCAAUCACCCUGUCACAGUGCUGAUCAGAGUAUACAUUGUCGCGGCAUUUAAUCUUAGUCCAGCUGAUCCAGAUGGCAAAUCAGAUCCCUACAUUGUGAUCAAGCUUGGCAAGACAGAAAUCAAAGACCGGGAUAAAUACAUCCCUAAACAACUGAACCCAGUAUUUGGAAGGUCAUUUGAGAUCCAAGCCACAUUCCCAAAAGAGUCCCUGCUCUCCAUCCUGAUCUAUGACCAUGACAUGAUUGGCACAGAUGACCUUAUUGGUGAGACCAAGAUCGACCUGGAGAACCGCUUCUACAGCAAACACCGAGCCAUCUGUGGCUUGCAGAGCCAGUAUGAGAUAGAAGGAUACAAUGCCUGGAGAGACACGUCCAAACCCACCGAAAUCCUCACUAAGCUCUGCAAAGACAACAAGCUGGAUGGACCCUACUUUCACCCUGGGAAAAUACAGAUAGGAAACCAAGUCUUUUCUGGAAAAACUAUCUUCACUGAAGAGGACACUGAUGAGACAGUGGAGUCUUAUGAACACCUGGCCCUCAAGGUUUUACACUCUUGGGAGGAUAUCCCGGAAGUCGGGUGUAGGCUGGUUCCUGAACACAUAGAAACUCGGCCACUGUACCACAAGGAUAAGCCAGGAAUGGAGCAGGGCCGCCUGCAGAUGUGGGUGGACAUGUUUCCCAAGGAUAUGCCUCAACCUGGACCUCCUGUUGACAUCUCUCCAAGGCGACCCAAAGGAUACGAAUUGAGAGUGACCAUCUGGAACACUGAAGAUGUCAUUUUAGAGGAUGAGAAUAUCUUCACAGGCCAAAAAUCAAGUGAUAUUUAUGUGAAAGGGUGGUUAAAGGGCUUGGAGGAUGACAAGCAGGAGACAGAUGUGCAUUACAACUCCCUGACUGGAGAGGGCAACUUCAACUGGCGCUUCCUGUUUCCCUUUCAGUAUCUCCCAGCUGAGAAGCAAAUGGUCAUUACCAAGAGGGAGAACAUCUUCUCUUUAGAGAAGAUGGAGUGUAAGACUCCUGCUGUGUUGGUGCUGCAGGUUUGGGAUUUUGAAAGGCUGUCCUCAGAUGACUUCCUGGGCACCCUGGAAAUGAACCUCAACAGUUUCCCUCGAGCAGCUAAGUCUGCCAAAGCCUGUGAUCUUGCCAAGUUUGAAAAUGCAAGUGAGGAGACCAAGAUCUCUAUAUUCCAGCAAAAACGUGUGCGUGGCUGGUGGCCUUUUUCUAAAAGCAAAGAACUCACAGGCAAGGUUGAAGCUGAGUUCCACCUAGUUACAGCAGAAGAAGCUGAGAAAAAUCCUGUUGGAAAAGCCCGAAAGGAGCCAGAGCCCCUGGCCAAGCCCAACCGCCCAGACACCUCCUUUUCGUGGUUCAUGAGCCCCUUUAAGUGCCUGUACUACCUCAUCUGGAAGAAUUACAAAAAGUACAUCAUCAUUGCUUUCAUUCUCAUCAUCCUCAUCAUCUUCCUCGUCCUUUUCAUCUACACCUUGCCAGGAGCCAUCAGCCGAAGGAUCGUUGUGGGCUCAUAGAGGAUCAUGGAGGACCCAGAUCCUCGCCAUAUACUAAUCCUCUCUUCCUUAUCUGGGAGCAUCUAAGAACAUGUCCCAUGCAUGGCACUGUGCUGAGUGCUAAGGGGACAGAUCAACCCUUCUUGGAAGAGAUGGAAAAGAAACAUUUCCUCCCUGCUCCAACCCCUGCCUCCAAGUUUCAAACUUGUAAGGCAUGUUUUAUCCCUUGGGCAGCAUGAAAUAAGGCACUUUCACCUCAUGGUAAUCAACAAUGACCUCAAAUUGACUUAGA